UUGGGCCUGGGUCUCUGCGCUAAAUGACUCCUGGGCAUCCUGCUGAACUCUCUCCCAGAAGGAGAUUGGCCUCACAUACCCCACUGACCCCUUCCUAGCAUGCUUUUUGCCAGACCCAUUGAGACUGGCUGAGGACUGGUUGCCAUAGAGAUGGCCUGUUAGGCAGUUCUACGGUGCGGAUGGGGGAUGGGGCAGGAUGGGGCAGGACACCGAUAUGCUAAAUACCUACCAACAGUUGGUUAGGACCCCGUCGGUGCGACCAGGGCAGGACGUGCGGCUCCAGGCUCCAGGAACCAGAACGGGGCUGCUCAAGCUGCUGUCGACCGUCUCUCAGGACAAGCAGGGCUGCCUGGGGAGUGGUGAUGGUGUGCCAAAUCAAGACCUGCAGCAGAGGUCUCAGAGCUCAAGGCAGACAGCAAAGAAGGACCGCAAGCCCAGGGGCCAGAGCAAGAAAGGACAGGGCUCUGAAGAGUCUGAAGAUCACUUCCCGCUUCUUCCUCGGAAACCCUCCUUCCCCUUCCAGUGGGCCUGGGAGAGCAUCGCCACAGAUGUCCGGGCUGUGCUUCAGCCAAGCUCCCCAACCCCUGGCCACCAAGCCCUGCCCAUGCCCUCCUCGUUCUCCCAGCGUCAGUCCAGGCGCAAGUCCACGGCCAACCUCCCAGAGGCCCAUGGCUGCUGCUGGAAGACAGAGGCGCAAAACCUGAAGGCGAGACAGCAGCUGGGAGCCUGGGGCGGUGUCUCCAUCCCUACUGGCAAAGGGGAGCUAGGAUCAGAGCCCCCCAGUGGUCUCCAGCUGCCUGGGAGGAGGCCAGGAUCAGGAUCGGCGUCCGACAAGCAGGUCCAGCUGCAAAGCCUGGGUGCUGAGGAGGCCGAGAGGGGUCUGAGUUCUGGGGUGCUGCCCCAGCGCCCCAGGAGGGGGUCGAUCUCAGAGGAGGAGCAAUUUUCAGAGGCCACAGAGGAGGCUGAGGAGGGAGAGCACAGGACUCCCUGCAGAAGGAGGGCUGGUUGUCAGAGAAAGGGGCAGAUUUCUGGAGAGGAAGCCUCCGAUGAGGGAGAAGUGCAGGGCCAGAGCCAGGGGAGCAGCCCCAGCUUCAACAACCUCCGAAGGCGACAAUGGAGGAAGACAAGGGCCAAGGAGCUGCAGGGGCCAUGGGACCUGGAGAAGCUGCACAGGCAGCUACAGAGAGACCUGGACUGUGGCCCCCAAAAGCUGCCCUGGAAGACUUUGAGGGCUGCCUUCCAGGCCUCCAAGCGGAAUGGAAAGGCCUAUGCCUCGGGAUACGAUGAAACUUUCGUGUCUGCCAACCUCCCUAAUCGCACCUUCCACAAACGACAGGAAGCCACCAGGAGCCUGCUGCAGGCCUGGGAGCGGCAGCGGCAGGAGGAGCGGCAGCAGGCCGAGCUGCGGCGGGCCCGGACACAGCAUGUACAGCGGCAGGUGGCCCACUGCCUGGCAGCCUACGCACCCAGAGGGAGCCGGGGCCCUGGGGCGGCCCAGCGCAAGCUGGAGGAGCUGAGGCGCCAGGAGCGACAGCGCUUUGCUGAGUACCAGGCGGAGCUGCAAGGCAUCCAGCACAGGGUGCAGGCCCGGCCCUUCCUGUUCCAGCAGGCUAUGCAGCCCUGGUGCAGAGCAGGAAGCCGUCUUCUCUCUCCUCAGGCCAAUGCCCGGCUCACCGUCACUCGGCGCUUCUCCCAGGUGCUGUCAGCACUGGGGCUGGAUGAGGAGCAGCUGCUGUCUGAGGCAGGAAAGGUGGACAGAGAGGGCACCCCCAGGAAACCCAGGAGCCACAGGUCAAUGGGGGUGAGAAUGGAGCACUCUCCUCAGAGGCCCCCAAGGACAGAACCCACCGGCAGCCAGCCUGACAGGCACUACAACCCCAGCCUGGACCCGGAGUGCAGUCCCUGAGAUAAAAUUAAAGGCUUUAUGGCAAA